AUGUCUUCGGCUACACUGGUGAAGGCAUCGUGCCUGCUCCACAGCACAUUUUUAUUCAAGAAUGUAUCUCCCGGAUGUCCAGAAUACGCCAUCUGCAAAACUGAACUCGUCCUCUUUCCCCAGAAUGUAUCUCCCGGAUGUCCAGAAUACGCCAUCUGCAAAACUGAACUCGUCCUCUUUCCCCCGAAUGUAUCAUCUCCCAGAUGUCCAGAAUACGCCAUCUGCAAAACUGAACUCGUCCUCUUUCCCCCGAAUGUAUCUCCCAGAUGUCCAGAAUACGCCAUCUGCAAAACUGAACUCAUCCUCUUUCCCCAGAAUGUAUCUCCCGGAUGUCGAGAAUACGCCAUCUGCAAAACUGAACUCGUCCUCUUUCCCCCGAAUGUAUCUCCCAGAUGUCCAGAAUACGCCAUCUGCAAAACUGAACUCGUCCUCUUUCCCCCGAAUGUAUCAUCUCCCAGAUGUCCAGAAUACGCCAUCUGCAAAACUGAACUCAUCCUCUUUCCCCAGAAUGUAUCUCGCGGAUGUCCAGAAUACGCCAUCUGCAAAACUGAACUCGUCCUCUUUCCCCCGAAUGUAUCUCCCGGAUGUCCAGAAUACGCCAUCUGCAAAACUGAACUCGUCCUCUUUCCCCAGAAUGUAUCUCCCGGAUGUCCAGAAUACGCCAUCUGCAAAACUGAACUCGUCCUCUUUCCCCCGAAUGUAUCUCCCGGAUGUCCAGAAUACACCAUCUGCAAAACUGAACUCGUCCUCUUUCCCCCGAAUGUAUCUCCCGGAUGUCCAGAAUACGCCAUCUGCAAAACUGAACUCGUCCUCUUUCCCCCGAAUGUAUCUCCCGGAUGUCCAGAAUACGCCAUCUGCAAAACUGAACUCGUCCUCUUUCCCCCGAAUGUAUCUCCCGGAUGUCCAGAAUACGCCAUCUGCAAAACUGAACUCGUCCUGUUUCCCCCGAAUGUAUCUCCCGGAUGUCCAGAAUACGCCAUCUGCAAAACUGAACUCGUCCUCUUUCCCCAGAAUGUAUCUCCCGGAUGUCCAGAAUACUCCAUCUGCAAAACUGAACUCAUCCUCUUUCCCCCGAAUGUAUCUCCCGGAUGUCCAGAAUACGCCAUCUGCAAAACUGAACUCGUCCUCUUUCCCCCGAAUGUAUCUCCCGGAUGUACAGAAUACGCCAUCUGCAAAACUGAACUCGUCCUCUUUCCCCCGAAUGUAUCUCCCGGAUGUCCAGAAUACGCCAUCUGCAAAACUGAACUCGUCCUCUUUCCCCAGAAUGUAUCUCCCGGAUGUCCAGAAUACGCCAUCUGCAAAACUGAACUCGUCCUCUUUCCCCCGAAUGUAUCUCCCGGAUGUCCAGAAUACGCCAUCUGCAAAACUGAACUCGUCCUCUUUCCCCCGAAUGUAUCUCCCGGAUGUCCAGAAUACGCCAUCUGCAAAACUGAACUCGUCCUGUUUCCCCCGAAUGUAUCUCCCGGAUGUCCAGAAUACGCCAUCUGCAAAACUGAACUCGUCCUCUUUCCCCAGAAUGUAUCUCCCGGAUGUCCAGAAUACUCCAUCUGCAAAACUGAACUCGUCCUCUUUCCCCCGAAUGUAUCUCCCGGAUGUCCAGAAUACUCCAUCUGCAAAACUGAACUCGUCCUCUUUCCCCAGAAUGUAUCUCCCGGAUGUCCAGAAUACGCCAUCUGCAAAACUGAACUCGUCCUCUUUCUCCCGAAUGUAUCUCCCGGAUGUCCAGAAUACGCCAUCUGCAAAACUGAACUCGUCCUCUUUCCCCCGAAUGUAUCUCCCGGAUGUCCAGAAUACGCCAUCUGCAAAACUGAACUCGUCCUCUUUCCCCCGAAUGUAUCUCCCGGAUGUCCAGAAUACGCCAUCGGCAAAACUGAACUCGUCCUCUUUCCCCAGAAUGUAUCUCCCGGAUGUCCAGAAUAUGCCAUCUGCAAAACUGAACUCGUCCUCUUUCCCCCGAAUGUAUCUCCCGGAUGUCCAGAAUACGCCAUCGGCAAAACUGAACUCGUCCUGUUUCCCCCGAAUGUAUCUCCCGGAUGUCCAGAAUACGCCAUCUGCAAAACAGAACUUGUCCUCUUUCCCCCAAAUGUGUGUCCACUGCUUGAACCAGGAAACUGGAUAUCAUCUUAAAUCCUCCCUUUCCCACCACCACCAAAUCCAAGCUGGGGAGCCCCUCUUCUUUACUGCCUCUGAAAACCGCACUGUCCCCCCACACCCCAUGGAUCCUGCUUGAACCCAGGCACUCAUCACUUCUUCGCUGGGGUAUGACCAUUCCCCUGGCCUUCCUAUCUUCCCAUCUAUGCCCAACAUGGCUGCCAAGGGGAUCUGUCCUAAAUGCAAAGUUAGCCAUGCCUGCCCUCCCUCCCCUGGCUUGCCUGAAAUCUUUCAGGAAGCUCAGAGCUUUUAAGACAACAUUUUGAGAACAAGGACCUUUUGCAAUUUUACGUCUUCUGUUUUCUGGAGUCCCCAAAUUCAGCUCAGCCUUCAUGGCUUCUAAGAAACUUGCCUUGACCUCAUCUUUCCUAUGCGUUCUGUGCCUAGCUAGCAAAAUUCUUAGCUGACAUUACUUUGAUCAUGAACUUUGUUGCCUGUGAGUUCCCAGAGGGCAGGCCAAGUCUGACUUGGCUUUGUUGCAAAGUCUAGCACAUGAUGGACAUUCAAUAAAGUUUUGAUAGAGAGAAAA